AGAGCCAGGCAGCAAGGACCAGAGGAAGGUGGACAGAGACCGAAAGGACAAAGGAGAGACACAGAGAAAAAAAGAGACCAACCCCAAAGGGACAAAGACCCCAACGUUUGUCCACAUUGCCGCAGAGGCAGCUGGAGCCAGUGCUGCCUGUCCGUCCCCAUGGGCCACCAUAGGCCAUGGCUGCACGCUUCUGUCCUCUGGGCUGGGGUGGCCAGCCUGCUCCUCCCCCCGGCCAUGACCCAGCAGCUCAGAGGGGAUGGGCUAGGCUUCAGAAACCGGAACAACAGCACUGGAGUCGCCGGGCUCUCCGAGGAGGCAUCAGCAGAGCUUCGCCACCACCUCCACAGCCCUAGAGACCAUCCAGAUGAGAACAAGGAUGUUUCCACAGAGAAUGGGCAUCAUUUCUGGAGCCACCCAGACCGUGAAAAGGAGGAUGAAGAUGUCUCCAAGGAAUAUGGGCACCUACUCCCAGGCCACAGGUCCCAAGACCACAAAGUCGGAGAUGAGGGUGUCUCAGGUGAGGAGGUCUUUGCAGAGCAUGGUGGGCAGGCCCGUGGGCACAGAGGCCACGGGAGUGAAGACACGGAAGACUCAGCUGAGCACAGGCACCACCUCCCCAGCCACAGGAGCCACAGCCAUCAAGACGAGGAUGAGGAUGAAGUUGUGUCCAGUGAGCAUCACCAUCAUAUCCUCAGGCAUGGACACCGAGGCCAUGAUGGGGAAGAUGAUGAAGGAGAAGAGGAGGAGGAGGAGGAGGAGGAGGAAGAGGAGGCCUCCACUGAGUAUGGACACCAGGCCCACAGGCACCGAGGCCAUGGGAGUGAAGAGGAUGAGGAUGUCUCAGAUGGACACCAUCAUCAUGGCCCCAGCCACAGGCACCAAGGCCAUGAAGAAGAUGACGAUGAUGAUGAUGAUGAUGAUGAUGAUGAUGAUGAUGAUGAUGUCUCCAUUGAAUAUAGACACCAGGCUCACAGGCACCAAGGCCACGGGAUUGAAGAGGAUGAAGAUGUCUCAGAUGGACACCAUCAUCGCGACCCCAGCCACAGGCACCGAAGCCAUGAAGAAGAUGACAAUGAUGAUGAUGAUGUCUCCACUGAGUAUGGACACCAGGCCCACAGGCACCAAGACCACAGAAAGGAAGAGGUUGAGGCUGUCUCAGGUGAACACCACCAUCAUGUCCCUGACCACAGGCACCAAGGCCACAGAGACGAGGAAGAAGAUGAGGAUGUGUCCACUGAACGUUGGCACCAGGGUCCCCAACAUGUCCACCAUGGCCUUGUAGAUGAGGAAGAGGAAGAAGAGGAGAUCACAGUCCAGUUCGGCCACUAUGUUGCAAGCCACCAACCUCGAGGCCACAAGAGUGAUGAAGAGGACUUCCAAGAUGAGUAUAAAACAGAAGUCCCUCACCAUCACCACCACAGAGUCCCCAGGGAGGAAGAUGAGGAGGUCUCUGCUGAGCUUGGCCACCAGGCCCCCAGCCACAGGCAAAGCCACCAAGAUGAAGAAACUGGCCAUGGUCAAAGAGGGUCCAUCAAAGAGAUGAGCCAUCACCCCCCAGGACACACAGUGGUCAAGGAUAGAAGCCAUUUGAGGAAGGAUGAUUCUGAGGAGGAAAAGGAGAAGGAAGAGGACCCCGGCUCCCAUGAGGAAGACGAUGAAAGUUCAGAGCAGGGAGAGAAAGGCACCCAUCAUGGCAGCCGGGACCAGGAAGAUGAGGAGGAUGAGGAGGAAGGUCAUGGCCUCAGCCUGAACCAGGAGGAGGAAGAAGAGGAAGACAAGGAGGAGGAGGAGGAGGAAGAAGACGAGGAGAGGAGGGAAGAGAGGGCUGAGGUUGGGGCCCCACUGAGCCCAGACCACAGCGAGGAGGAAGAGGAGGAGGAGGAGGGGCUGGAGGAAGAUGAGCCCCGCUUCACCAUCAUCCCCAACCCACUGGACAGGAGAGAGGAGGCUGGAGGUGCCUCCAGCGAGGAGGAAAGCGGUGAGGACACAGGUCCACAGGAUGCUCAGGAGUAUGGGAACUACCAGCCAGGGUCCCUGUGUGGCUACUGCUCCUUCUGCAAUCGAUGCACUGAAUGUGAGAGCUGUCACUGUGAUGAGGAGAACAUGGGUGAGCACUGCGACCAGUGCCAGCACUGUCAGUUCUGCUAUCUCUGCCCGCUGGUCUGCGAAACGGUCUGCGCUCCAGGAAGCUACGUUGACUAUUUCUCCUCGUCCCUUUAUCAGGCCCUGGCAGACAUGCUGGAAACGCCGGAACCCUGACCCAGUCGCUCGACUGCGACGCAGGUGUACCUCCCCCUGCCUUCCAACCCCUUUCCACGAGCUAUAUUUAUUUCUCCGAAUAAACGUGCUCCCCGAAA